UGCCGGGGCCCCAAGUCUGGCCGGGAAGCGCGCGCGCCCGACGAGCACGCGCGCCCGACGAGCACGCGCGCGGCACUGACGCAACUGAGCCCUCGGUCCGAGCUCGCUCCCGACAUCGCCUAGCUGCGCUGACGUAGGGAAAAAUCCAGUCCCCGGCGCGAGAAUAGGAUUUCUAAACCGGCGGUGGCAACCAGCACUAGUCGGCCCGCCAGUCAUAUCCGCCCCGCCCCGUCGGCUGCCGGGCACGCCCACCUAGGGGGGUCGACGGAUCCGAUUGGAGAACGCAUUCGGCGCAAAAGAAGGAGGAGCAUGAGACCCAGAAGAGGAAUCGAGAAGCAGAAGCAGAGGGCGGAGUAGCCCCGCCCGUCUGCUCGACCUUUUCUAGUUGGUUGGCGGAGAAUCACGCCAUUUUUUAACAUCUCUUUUUGAUCAAACAAGAAAAGGCAUUUGGGAAAUGCAAAGAGGACUGAGAAUACUUUGGCUUAAAUUUUGCCCCCAGAAUCUUGUUGUUUGCCUACUGAAGAGAUGAAACCAUGGCAGAAGUAGAAUCCUUAUAGAAACAGGACCAGAAACACCUCCCUUCUCCAACAAAAGGUUCAUUUUGGUGGCUGUCCGUUUGACCUGCUGUGCUUCAGUUUAAUUGGCUUGGAAAGGGGUCAGCAGGGUGAAACCGAACCCCAGAAAACUUGAUGAAGAAAUGUCUUUUGCCCGUUUUGAUUACGUGCAUGCAAACAGCGAUUUGCAAAGACCGUAUGAUGAUGAUCAUGAUCUUACUGGUGAAUUACAGACCUGAUGAAUUUAUAGAAUGUGAAGACCCAGUGGAUCAUGUUGGAAAUGCAACUGCAUCCCAGGAACUUGGUUAUGGUUGUCUCAAGUUCGGCGGUCAGGCCUACAGCGACGUGGAACACACUUCAGUCCAGUGCCAUGCCUUAGAUGGAAUUGAGUGUGCCAGUCCUAGGACCUUUCUACGAGAAAAUAAACCUUGUAUAAAGUAUACCGGACACUACUUCAUAACCACUUUACUCUACUCCUUCUUCCUGGGAUGUUUUGGUGUGGAUCGAUUCUGUUUGGGACACACUGGCACUGCAGUAGGGAAGCUGUUGACGCUUGGAGGACUUGGGAUUUGGUGGUUUGUUGACCUUAUUUUGCUAAUUACUGGAGGGCUGAUGCCAAGUGAUGGCAGCAACUGGUGCACUGUUUACUAAGAAGAGCUGCCAUCAUGGCCCAGGGAGGCGGGUGAAAGCUCCGUCUUCUGAAUUCAUCUCUACAGGCUCAAAACUCCUCUUUGAUAUCAGACCUGAUGUUAUUUUCCUUCUUUUGGAGGGCAUUUGUUUGGUUAAGAAGGCUUCUUUGGACUUUGGAAUUUCAACCCAGAUUUUACCUUGCAGACGGAAUGACAAGCAAAAAGUGUUGUGGGGAAUCAAAUUUGUUCCUUUCCUCAUGCACAAAACAUAAAGGAUAGUGGCGAGUUUACAAGCUGUGGAUGGGUUUCCAUAGUCUUCCUUUCUGUACAUUGCUAUAUCUUCAGUCCUUUGGAGCAAGUGGACCUAACAAGUUGAGCAAAAUGAAUAUUUGGAUCCAUGUUCCUCUUGUGACCCUGAGUCUUCAUGCAAGGAGAUCUGAAGCUGAACAAUGAAAAUCUUCAGCAGAAAUAGAAAUGGCCGUGGAUUGUAAUACACACUGAAAUUCUGACUUUCUGAAUUUAAAUGUAGAAUAAAUUUUACCAACUUGGAGUACUGUAUGAGUAUUUUCAGUAGGGGGAAUAAACUCAAAAUUAUAUUUGUUUUGCAGAAACCUAGUCAUUUGAAAUGAGCCAUCCUAUUAAGCCCUCUUUUGUCUCCAUUAUGUUCCAGAGGCAGUAUAUGCAGUGCAAUAAUUUUUUCAUUCCACUUAUGUUUUGAAAGCCAGCGGCAUCAGAUGUGUGAGUUGAGCUAUUCCUCCUGGCAGAAUUGUCCAAUCUAAAAAUCAGCGUUUACCAGCCCAUGCUAAUAAAAUUAAGAUUUCAUACAAGUUUCUGUAAAACUAUUCUUCAUGAUUAGCUCUCCCUGUGGGCUGCAGCAGUCAGAAAGAGAUAACAGCCACACCUCUGCAUUCCCCGGUCACCAGGAAUAAAAGGAAAUGUUCCAGAUUGUAAGUGGUUUUAAAAACUCAGUUCUCAUCGUUUGCAAUCUAAGUUGAAAGAACUAUUAAAUAUAAAAUCAAAGGUGGGCAAUGUGGCCAAGUCAAUGGAAGAGGCUUUACUCAGAAUAACUUACAAAUUCUAGAAACAAGGUAGAACUCACUCAGUUUACCUAAUAAUAAUUGAAUUUAAGACCAAAUAUCACAGUUGAAAUAACUUCCCUGGAUACAUUCUAUCAUUUUGUAGCUUUCCUAAGAAUUUCUUGCUUUAUCAUUCCUGAUUAAUCACUGUUUUUACAUUAUUAAAGGUGGCAAUUUUCUGUAAAAAAUUUAAAACAGAUGAUCCUAUUCUGUCUUGAAAGUUCUGUACCACACUGACCUUAACCUUGCUUAUAACAUAACAAUUGGUAAACUUUUAAUUCAUAAUCUUUAUACCCUAAGAUAGUAUUUAUUAAAUUUUUAUGGGUCAUGAAGAAACUAGACCCUCUCCCCAGAAAAAUCUACAUACACAGAAUUUACAUAGAACUUGGGUUCAUCUACACAAUUUAUGCAUGAAAUAAAAUUGUACUGGUACCCUAUAAAUUUAUACAAAUAAAAGAGUUUAAGGGAGUUCAAGGAUGCCAUAUGUAUAUUUUAAAAAAAUUUCUAAGGGAAGUCUAAAAAACAUAAAUUAUAAUAUUACCCAAAAUAAGAUGCUACUUUUCACCUAACCAAGUCCUGCCUCAUUUCACACUUUAACCUCCUAAGUAUAUUCAUAACCCUACCAAAAGUUGUUUUCUUUAAAAAAUAAGAAACUUUAGGGCCAGCGCAAUGGUGCAAGCCUGUAAUCCCUGCACUUUGGGAGGCCGAGGCAGGUGAAUCCUUUAAGGUCAGGAGUUCGAGACCAGCCUGGCCAACAUGGUGAGACACACUCCCCCACCCCCGCCCAGUCUCUAGUAAAAAUGCAAAAAUUAGCCGGGCGUGGUGGCGUGCACCUGUAAUCCCAGCUACUCGGGAGGCUGAGGUAAGAGAAUCACUUGAACUGAGGAGGCAGAGAUUGCAGUGAGCCGAGAUCCUGCCACUGCACUUCAGCCUGGGCAACAGAGUGAGACUCUGACCAAAAAAGAAAUUUUGCAGCUCCAAGGCUUGAAGUCAUUUAUGUUGCCAGGGGUAAGAGCUUGGUUGAAGGGCUAAAAGACUAGAAACUACUGAAGAUGCCCUUCUUACUGUCAGUAAAGCUGCUGGAGACAAAAGAAGUUGUUCUCGCUGCUAGAGUGGUAAUUUGAGAAUCAUCAGUAUUCCUAUGUGACAAUCCAAAAUUACUGGUUUUCAUUUGACUUGUAAAUGACACCCAUCAUCCAUCUGCCCACAAACCUGGCCAAAUGUGAUACAACCUGAAAACCUGAUGGACUAAAGGAGUACUAUUUAACAAUUGAUUGCCUUUGCACUUUAUUCAGGUUGUUUCUUAAAUUUUGGUAGACAGAUCCAUUUGUAUAUGUGUGUGUUAUAUCUAGUUUAUGGCUAUAGAGAAGGUUUAAAAUACUACAGUGUCCUUCCCUCAAGGUUAAAUUAGAAGCUGCCUGCCUUUUAGUUGUUUCUUGCCUUUAAUAAAAUGUUAUCAGUUCCCCCAGA